ACGCUGCCGCCGGCAUCCGCUCGGACGCGGCCACGUUGUCUUGCGCGCUUUGCCCGCCUGGCCCUGGGACUCUGACCCUCGGCUACCCUUUCCUGCCCCACUAGCGUGGCCGCGAGCCUCGGUGAGCCGGCCGUAUUCCCGCUCUCGCUUAGGGGGCACAGGCGCAGGCAUCGGCCCGGCCACUCCAAGCCUUCGGUGCGCGGGCGCGUCUGGGAUACGGGCCCGGGAGGCGCCGCCCUCCGUCCGCCCGGUGCCUCUCAGGAACAGCGAACCGGAGAGAGCGCCGGAGAGUUGGGCUCAGUGCAGAGCUCGGCGCCGGGGCCCAUGCCCGUGCGCCCCCGCAGGCCGGCGCCAUGGCCUCCGGGAGUGUGGCCGAGUGCCUGCAGCAGGAGACCACCUGCCCCGUGUGCCUGCAGUACUUCGCAGAGCCCAUGAUGCUCGACUGCGGCCAUAACAUCUGUUGCGCGUGCCUCGCCCGCUGCUGGGGCACGGCAGAGACUAACGUGUCGUGCCCGCAGUGCCGGGAGACCUUCCCGCAGAGGCACAUGCGGCCCAACCGGCACCUGGCCAACGUGACCCAACUGGUAAAGCAGCUGCGCACCGAGCGGCCGUCGGGGCCCGGCGGCGAGAUGGGCGUGUGCGAGAAGCACCGCGAGCCCCUGAAGCUGUACUGCGAGGAGGACCAGAUGCCCAUCUGCGUGGUGUGCGACCGCUCCCGCGAGCACCGCGGCCACAGCGUGCUGCCGCUCGAGGAGGCGGUGGAGGGCUUCAAGGAGCAAAUCCAGAACCAGCUCGACCAUUUAAAAAGAGUGAAAGAUUUAAAGAAGAGACGUCGGGCCCAGGGGGAACAGGCACGAGCUGAACUCUUGAGCCUAACCCAGAUGGAGAGGGAGAAGAUUGUUUGGGAGUUUGAGCAGCUGUAUCACUCCUUAAAGGAGCAUGAGUAUCGCCUCCUGGCCCGCCUUGAGGAGCUAGACUUGGCCAUCUACAAUAGCAUCAAUGGUGCCAUCACCCAGUUCUCUUGCAACAUCUCCCACCUCAGCAGCCUGAUCGCUCAGCUAGAAGAGAAGCAGCAGCAGCCCACCAGGGAGCUCCUGCAGG